GUCUGCUCUCAGCGGCGGCGGCAGGGGCUGAGGGCACAGCCAGCGGGCGGCGCGCCGCGGACUCCAAGGCAGCCCGCCAAAAGAAUCCUGAACAUCAUCAUAAAAAGACAGUCACCAGUCCUGCUCAUCUGGAGGACUGUUCUCACAAUCUUCAGCAAGGAGAUAAAACAGAGUACUGCAGAGAUGAAGUAACUUGCCCUAAGACCCAUACCUGAAUUAACAGCUCUGAAAUUUGAAGGUGCUAGUGUCUCACUGGUCUUAAACUGCGAAGCUGAACGACGAAAGCAUCCUUCCUGUAAUCAGUGUAGCAAAAUGACAGGCAGAGAAACCAUGCUGGGAAGAAGCAAGGUCAUCAGUUGAACCAUCUUGACUUUGGCCCAGAACACAGCUCAGCCUCAACUCCUGCAGUGCAUUUGCCUCCCUCACUUUGGUUUAAGACCUGGAGUGAUGUGUUCCUGCUCCAGAGCACCUUUCUUUCUGUGAGGCCCGAAACAUGACCACCAGCGGCCACGCAUGUCCGGUCCCAGCAGUGAACGGACACAUGACUCACUAUCCAGCCACACCCUACCCGUUACUCUUUCCACCUGUCAUCGGAGGACUUUCCCUGCCUCCCCUCCAUGGCCUUCAUGGACAUCCGCCUCCGAGUGGAUGCAGCACCCCGUCGCCGGCAACAAUUGAAACACAGAGCACCAGCUCUGAGGAACUCGUCCCAAGCCCCCCAUCUCCACUUCCUCCCCCUCGAGUGUACAAACCCUGCUUCGUCUGCCAGGACAAAUCAUCAGGGUACCACUAUGGGGUCAGCGCCUGUGAGGGAUGUAAGGGCUUUUUCCGCAGAAGUAUUCAGAAGAAUAUGAUUUACACUUGUCACCGAGAUAAGAACUGUGUUAUUAAUAAAGUCACCAGGAAUCGAUGCCAAUACUGUCGACUCCAGAAGUGCUUUGAAGUGGGAAUGUCCAAAGAAUCUGUCAGGAAUGACAGGAACAAGAAAAAGAAGGAGACUUCGAAGCAAGAAUGCACAGAGAGCUAUGAAAUGACAGCUGAGUUGGACGAUCUCACAGAGAAGAUCCGAAAAGCUCACCAGGAAACUUUCCCUUCACUCUGCCAGCUGGGUAAAUACACCACGAAUUCCAGUGCUGACCAUCGAGUCCGACUGGACCUGGGCCUCUGGGACAAAUUCAGUGAACUGGCCACCAAGUGCAUUAUUAAGAUCGUGGAGUUUGCUAAACGUCUGCCUGGUUUCACUGGCUUGACCAUCGCAGACCAAAUUACCCUGCUGAAGGCCGCCUGCCUGGACAUCCUGAUUCUUAGAAUUUGCACCAGGUAUACCCCAGAACAAGACACCAUGACUUUCUCAGACGGCCUUACCCUAAAUCGAACUCAGAUGCACAAUGCUGGAUUUGGUCCUCUGACUGACCUUGUGUUCACCUUUGCCAACCAGCUCCUGCCUUUGGAAAUGGAUGACACAGAAACAGGCCUUCUCAGUGCCAUCUGCUUAAUCUGUGGAGACCGCCAGGACCUUGAGGAACCGACAAAAGUAGAUAAGCUACAAGAACCAUUGCUGGAAGCACUAAAAAUUUAUAUCAGAAAAAGACGACCCAGCAAGCCUCACAUGUUUCCAAAGAUCUUAAUGAAAAUCACAGAUCUCCGUAGCAUCAGUGCUAAAGGUGCAGAGCGUGUAAUUACCUUGAAAAUGGAAAUUCCUGGAUCAAUGCCACCUCUCAUUCAAGAAAUGCUGGAGAAUUCUGAAGGACAUGAACCCUUGACCCCAAGUUCAAGUGGGAACACAGCAGAGCACAGUCCUAGCAUCUCACCCAGCUCAGUGGAAAACAGUGGGGUCAGUCAGUCACCACUCGUGCAAUAAGACAUUUUCUAGCUACUUCAAACAUUCCCCAGUACCUUCAGUUCCAGGAUUUAAAAUGCAAGAAAAAACAUUUUUACUGCUGCUUAGUUUUUGGACUGAAAAGAUAUUAAAACUCAAGAAGGACCAAGAAGUUUUCAUAUGUAUCAAUAUAUAUACUCCUCACUGUGUAACUUACCUAGAAAUACAAACUUUUCCAAUUUUAAAAAAUCAGCCAUUUCAUGCAACCAGAAACUAGUUAAAAGCUUCUAUUUUCCUCUUUGAACACUCAAGAUUGCAUGGCAAAGACCCAGUCAAAAUGAUUUACCCCUGGUUAAGUUUCUGAAGACUUUGUACAUACAGAAGUAUGGCUCUGUUCUUUCUAUACUGUAUGUUUGGUGCUUUCCUUUUGUCUUGCAUACUCAAAAUAACCAUGACACCAAGGUUAUGAAAUAGACUACUGUACACGUCUACCUAGGUUCAAAAAGAUAACUGUCUUGCUUUCAUGGAAUAGUCAAGACAUCAAGGUAAGGAAACAGGACUAUUGACAGGACUAUUGUACAGUAUGACAAGAUAAGGCUGAAGAUAUUCUACUUUAGUUAGUAUGGAAGCUUGUCUUUGCUCUUUCUGAUGCUCUCAAACUGCAUCUUUUAUUUCAUGUUGCCCAGUAAAAGUAUACAAAUUCCCUGCACUAGCAGAAGAGAAUUCUGUAUCAGUGUAACUGCCAGUUCAGUUAAUCAAAUGUCAUUUGUUCAAUUGUUAAUGUCACUUUAAAUUAAAAGUGGUUUAUUACUUGUUUAAUGACAUAACUACACAGUUAGUUAAAAAAAAUUUUUUUACAGUAAUGAUAGCCUCCAAGGCAGAAACACUUUUCAGUGUUAAGUUUUUGUUUACUUGUUCACAAGCCAUUAGGGAAAUUUCAUGGGAUAAUUAGCAGGCUGGUCUACCACCUGGACCAUGUAACUCUAGUGUCCUUCCUGAUUCAUGCCUGAUAUUGGGAUUUUUUUUUCCAGCCUUCUUGAUGCCAAGGGGCUAAUUAAUAUUAACAACUCCCAAAGAAACAGGCAUAGAAUCUGCCUCCUUUGACCUUGUUCAAUCACUAUGAAGCAGAGUGAAAGCUGUGGUAGAGUGGUUAACAGAUACAAGUGUCAGUUUCUUAGUUCUCAUUUAAGCACUAGUGGAAUUUUUUUUUUUUGAUAUAUUAGCAAGUCUGUGAUGUACUUUCACUGGCUCUGUUUGUACAUUGAGAUUGUUUGUUUAACAAUGCUUUCUAUGUUCAUAUACUGUUUACCUUUUUCCAUGGAGUCUCCUGGCAAAGAAUAAAAUAUAUUUAUUUUAAA